GUCACCCUCUUCCCCCCUUUUGGGCUGGAGGCUCCACCUUUUGUGUUUCCCGCACAGUCAAUCAAAAUAGGAAAAAAAAAUCCCCGGACCGCUCCGGCCGUGUCCGCCGCCGCUUCCCGCAUCCUCUCCCGCCGCCGCCGCCUUCGCUCCUCACCAUGUGUAAGGCGGCGGGGAGCCCCGCCUGAGGUGCCCUAAACACACUAUGACCGCUCCCGAAAAGCCCGUGAAACAAGAGGAAAUGGCUGCCUUGGACGUGGAUAGCGGCGGCGGCGGUGGCGGCGGCGGCGGCCACGGCGAGUAUCUGCAGCAGCAGCAACAGCACGGAAACGGUGCGGUGGCGGCGGCAGCGGCGGCCCAGGACACUCAGCCGUCACCGCUCGCUCUGCUGGCCGCUACCUGCAGCAAGAUAGGGCCGCCAUCGCCGGGCGACGACGAGGAGGAGGCGGCCGCCGCAGCCGGGGCCCCCGCCGCCGCCGGAGCGACAGGUGAUUUGGCUUCUGCACAGUUAGGAGGAGCACCAAACCGAUGGGAGGUUUUGUCAGCCACACCUACAACUAUAAAAGAUGAAGCUGGUAAUCUAGUCCAGAUUCCAAGUGCUGCUACUUCAAGUGGGCAGUAUGUUCUUCCCCUUCAGAAUUUGCAGAAUCAACAAAUAUUUUCCGUUGCACCAGGAUCAGAUUCAUCAAAUGGUACAGUGUCCAGUGUUCAAUAUCAAGUGAUACCACAGAUCCAGUCAGCAGAUGGUCAGCAGGUUCAAAUUGGUUUCACAGGCUCUUCAGAUAAUGGGGGUAUAAAUCAAGAAAGCAGUCAAAUUCAGAUCAUUCCUGGCUCUAAUCAAACCUUACUUGCCUCUGGAACACCUUCUGCUAACAUCCAGAAUCUCAUACCACAGACUGGUCAAGUCCAGGUUCAGGGAGUUGCAAUUGGUGGUUCAUCUUUUCCUGGUCAAACCCAAGUAGUUGCUAAUGUGCCUCUUGGUCUGCCAGGAAAUAUUACGUUUGUACCAAUCAAUAGUGUCGAUCUAGAUUCUUUGGGACUCUCGGGCAGUUCUCAGACAAUGACUGCAGGCAUUAAUGCCGACGGACAUUUGAUAAACACAGGACAAGCUAUGGAUAGUUCAGACAAUUCAGAAAGGACUGGUGAGCGGGUUUCUCCUGAUAUUAAUGAAACUAAUACUGAUACAGAUUUAUUUGUGCCAACAUCCUCUUCAUCACAGUUGCCUGUUACGAUAGAUAGUACAGGUAUAUUACAACAAAACACAAAUAGCUUGACUACAUCUAGUGGGCAGGUUCAUUCUUCAGAUCUUCAGGGAAAUUAUAUCCAGUCGCCUGUUUCUGAAGAGACACAGGCACAGAAUAUUCAGGUUUCUACAGCACAGCCUGUUGUACAGCAUCUACAACUUCAAGAGUCUCAGCAGCCAACCAGUCAAGCCCAAAUUGUGCAAGGUAUUACACCACAGACAAUCCAUGGUGUGCAAGCCAGUGGUCAAAAUAUAUCACAACAGGCUUUGCAAAAUCUUCAGUUGCAGCUGAAUCCUGGAACCUUUUUAAUUCAGGCACAGACAGUGACCCCUUCUGGACAGGUAACUUGGCAAACGUUUCAAGUACAAGGGGUCCAGAACUUGCAGAAUUUGCAAAUACAGAAUACUGCUGCCCAACAAAUAACUUUGACGCCUGUUCAAACCCUCACACUUGGUCAAGUUGCGGCAGGUGGAGCCUUCACUUCAACUCCAGUUAGUCUAAGCACUGGUCAGUUGCCAAAUCUACAAACAGUUACAGUGAACUCUAUAGAUUCUGCUGGUAUACAGCUACAUCCAGGAGAGAAUGCUGACAGUCCUGCAGAUAUUAGGAUCAAGGAAGAAGAACCUGAUCCUGAAGAGUGGCAGCUCAGUGGUGAUUCUACCUUGAAUACCAAUGACCUAACACACUUAAGAGUACAGGUGGUAGAUGAAGAAGGGGACCAACAACAUCAAGAAGGAAAAAGACUUCGGAGGGUAGCUUGCACCUGUCCCAACUGUAAAGAAGGUGGUGGAAGAGGUACCAAUCUUGGGAAAAAGAAGCAACACAUUUGUCAUAUACCAGGAUGUGGUAAAGUCUAUGGGAAGACCUCACAUCUGAGAGCUCAUCUGCGUUGGCAUUCUGGAGAACGCCCUUUUGUUUGUAACUGGAUGUACUGUGGUAAAAGAUUUACUCGAAGUGAUGAAUUACAGAGGCACAGAAGAACACAUACAGGUGAGAAGAAAUUUGUUUGUCCAGAAUGUUCAAAACGCUUUAUGAGAAGUGACCACCUUGCCAAACAUAUUAAAACACACCAGAAUAAAAAAGGUAUUCACUCUAGCAGUACAGUGCUGGCAUCUGUGGAAGCUGCGCGAGAUGAUACUUUGAUUACUGCAGGAGGAACAACGCUUAUCCUUGCAAAUAUUCAACAAGGUUCUGUUUCAGGGAUAGGAACUGUUAAUACUUCCGCCACCAGCAAUCAAGAUAUCCUUACCAACACUGAAAUACCUUUACAGCUUGUCACAGUUUCUGGAAAUGAGACAAUGGAGUAAAUAUUACACAAAUACUUAUUCAUUGUGGUUAUUUUUAUACAGUAGUGAGAAGAAUAUUGUUCCUAAGUUCUUAGAUAUCUUUUUAUUGAUGUGCAAAAAUUUUUGGAUUGACAGUAACUUGGUUAUACAUGACACUGAAAUGCCUUACUUUGUAUGAUAUUCCAUAGUAUAUUAAAAAUGGUAAAAUUGCAUGGGUUUUGUAGGUACUUUUGGAAUCUAGAAGAAAUGAAAUUUUACCAAGUUAUAUAAAGAGAAAAUUGAAUUUAACAAUGCGAAUGGUAGUCUAACCAAAUGCAUCAAUCCUGUGUGGUUUAGUGUAAAAAUGAGAACAUGUUGGUAUUUAUCUAUUGUAAGAUAAAAAAGCUGGUGGGUGAAAGAAAUCAUGUUAUGAUAAAAAAUUUUGUAAUUUUCUUGAUGACUGGAAUUUUUAUUAUGCAUAACUGACAAAUCAAGUUUCCAAGCAAAUGUUACAUAGUGUAGGCUUUACUUAGCUUAUCAAUUUGUCAUUUUGAAGCUAAUUAUUUUAAUUAGGUUAACUAUGUACAAUAUUUUAAGCAUUACUCUUGUAAGAUUUUGAAAACUACAUUUUAACAUGGAACUCUAGGGAUAGUCACCUUUUAAAUCCUGUUGAAAAGCCAUGUUUAAGAUUUAAUUUGCCAAAAUAAUGUCUUGUUAAUAUUCUUUCAAUAACGAAGUUGGGCAAUAUAACCAAUGUUUAAAAAAGUUUAAAAUGUAUAAGUUGAGGCAUUUGGGUGGUAAGAGAAUGUUAUAGUGAAUUAUCCCUUUUCUUGACUAUUGGAGGACCAAAAAAAUAAGGUGUAUUGCGUCUUAGCAGUGAUUUUUAUCCAAUCUUGUUUCCAAAAACCAUGUCUCCCAGGGCCUUAAAAGCCAUCAUGUAAAUUACCAGUAAAGUGUAACAUAUGCAAACAUAACAAAAUCACUUCCAUAGUGACGAUACUCCAACCAUAUGGAUAUUAGUCAUAGAAGAACUAGAGGUUUUAUGAUAUUUUUUUAAGUCUUUUUUUUUUUUGUCUAGGUAGUCAGUCUGCACUUAAAUAUCAAUCAUUUUCCUUUUUUGCUUCUUCCCUUAAAAUUUAUAUGUAUCCAGUACAUUUAAUUGAGAAGCGUAUGUUUUUUAUUAUGCUGUAUUUUCUUUUUAUUUUUUAAUUAUUGUUUAUAUUUUCAAUUCAAAAAUGUACAAAAUAAAGUUACAUUGCUGGUCUUGUAAGAGCUAUACAGUUUUCCUAAAUGUAUACCUGUAACUGCAGCAGUUCACCUAUUUCAAAAAUUUGGAAUUCUGUUCAUUUGUUAUUCUUAAGACCACCUCAAAUUUAAAGGCUACCUUAUUGUACGUUUAAAGUGUAUUAUAACAGUGUGGUAGUUAAUAAAACACUAUUUUUUUUUCUUUUGAGUUUGUUGUAUUCCUAUGCAUAAAAAAUAUUGCAGUGGUAUGGGGUAAGAAUUGGUGGUUUAUUUUUCUUCAACUUGGCUUUUUAUUUUUAGAUUCUUGAUUUUAGACACUGAAUUGUAAACAGGCAUUUAUUUGAAGAAGAGAUAUAUAGAGACACUGGUCAUUUACUAAUUUUUUACCUAGAGUAAAUAAGAAUGAGCUUAUUAAAUAAAAUUUUUGAAAAAAAGUCUUAGCCCUUAGCCCACAUUGAUUCAUAUCAGUUUUAUCAGUACCAUUUUGCAAUUUUUUUGUUUUCCGUUUUAAAGCAAUGCAGAAUAUUUUGAUUUAUCGAAAACCUGAAUUUACAUUAAGACUCCUGAAAAUGAUAAGACAAGCGUUGGUAACCAUGGCAGGAGUUACUUGAAAAAGUUGCCUUUGAAUUUGCAUGUGUUUCAUCAUUAUAAAGGCAGAGUAGGAGGAAAGAGUAUUAAUGUGAUUGUGUAUUGUAGAUGUUUUAAAGUAAAAAUCAAGUUUCUUAACACAUGUAUACAGUGGGGGUAAAGAUGUCCAUUUUCUGUUUUCCAGGCCCAGUCUGACUCUGUCUGUAAUACCUGAUUGCAUUGGAGAACUCUAGACACGCAUAAACAUGGACAGUUUUUCUAAAUGUGAGACUUAAGCCUGUGAUGUAAAAUAGGAAGUUCUACUUGGAAUAAUAUAAAGGAACCACUAGAAUUUACAAUUAUUUUGAAGUUACAGGGAUUAGAUUUUGAAUCUUAAAAUCCUUUAGGUAAUUUUUAGAAUUUUUAAAUUAAGAUUAAUGUGAAGAGAAUUAAGUGAGCAGCAGGUGGUUCACUUGAGCAAACUGCCCAUUAAGUCAGAUUAAACCAUUUGAAUGAUAGUAGAGAUGUUUUAAGUAAUACUGGAUUUUUACAGUAAGUUUAUGGUGUACUUUGAAUCGAUAGGUGUCCAUGCAUAUUUUAUGAAUUCGUGGAGAAUGAAUGCAAUGAAGAAAGUAAGUAGUCUUGAAAAUUAUUUAAAUAAAGUUGUAGAUUUUUUUAGUGCCCCCUAGGAAUAUAUUAGUGAACUUUGGAACUUUUACCAAAGUUAUGUAACCUCAGUGUAGAUAAUUUUAAAUAUUUCUAUUUUUAUAUUUUAAAAUGUUGAAUAUACUCUGGAAACAACAUUUGAAGAUUUGCUCUGAUGUCAACUUUUUCUGGUUAUAAAACCUAUUAGUAUUGUGUAUAAUUCUCAGGGUAGGUAUACUCUAAUAGGUGUUUUGUCAAUUGCUUUAUUUUUGUAAAGGCUAGAGUUAGUGCAUAUUGAAUAUAUUUAUGUACAAAUAAUUCCUGUUGUAACAUUUAGUGGACGCGAUUAUCUGUAUACCUCAAAUUUUAAUUUAAGAAAGUAUCACUUAAAGAGCAUCUCAUUUUCUAUAGAUUGAGGCUUAAUUACUGAAAAGUGACUCAACCAAAAAGCACAUAACCUUUUAAAGGAGCUACACCUACCGCAGAAAGUCAGAUGCCCUGUAAAUAACUUUGGUCUUUCAAAAUAGUGGCAAUGCUUAAGAUACUUAAAAAUACACAUACAUAUAAGCUGAAAGCAUGUCAAGCCUAUUUCAUAGAAAAUAGUUCUUAAACAGUAUUGUUCAUUAGAAAUUGCUGGGGAGCAUUUUAGAGAUUCCAUAGGCCUGGUAGCCACCUCAGCUUACUAAAUCAACAUCUCUGGAGAUGGAGUGUAUAUGUGUUUUGAAACAGCUGCUCAAGUGGUUCUGUUAAACACUCCUGCGUUACAAUCACUUAAAAUAGAGCAAGCAUCCCCUUAGGCUCUUAAUUGUAGUUUAAAUUCCAGUACUGCCUACUCAGACCCAAAAGUUUUGUUUUAUGAAAAAUUUGUAUUGUGUUCAAUAUUGUUUGAAAUUUGGGGUUGUUGCAUAAAUGAUUAUGGAAUAACAUUUGGUUUUAAAAUAAUAUAAACUGACAUGUUAUGCUACCUGUUACACAAUUUGGUUUUCAGUUUUAAUUAUAUGAAGCUGGUAACAAUCGUUUUUGUUGUAAAAGAAUUAUUUUUCACUAAACAGUAUGUUUAAAACUGACUGCCAUGAAUGAGUACUAAGUCUUUUGUUGUCUGACAAUAAGCACAAAACAAAUUAAUUGAUAUCUUUGGUACAAAUUUGAUAUUUUUGUGAAAUCACCUCAUAAUUUUAUUUAGUGUUGAAGAAACAACAUUGGCCCCUUGCCUUGUUCAGACAGAUUUGCGUAUAAUGUAAAUAUAUAUAUUAGUGGCAGAAACAAAGUACUGUAGAAACCUAGAAGAGGGAGAAUUCUGCAUGAAGUCUGGGAAACUCAGCAGAAAUGGCGUUUGCAAAGGUACAGUGUGGUAUGUUGGGUGAUGGGGGACUUUGUGAGGGACAGAGUGGAAAAAUUUUUAAGAGGGGCUGCCAAAUUGCAAAAGAGAAGAAUUUUUUUUGUCAGUGAUUCCUAGUCUUUUUGGAAUCCUACACCUUCUCCCCAGAAAAAUUCAUUCUAGUCCAGGGUUUAUUGUUUGUUUUUUCCCUAUAUUUGACAGGGUCUGUCUCUGUCACACAGUGCAGUGGUGCAAUCAUGGCUUACUGCAGACUCCACUUACUGGUCUCAAGCAAUCCUCCCCACUUCGGCCUCUUAAGUAGCUUGGACCACAGGUGCACACCACCAUGCUCAGUUAAUUUUAAUUUGUUUUGUAGAGAUGGGGUCUCACUAUAUUGCCUAGGCUGGUCUUGAAUUCCUGGGCUCAAGUGAUCCUUCCACCUCUGCCUCCCAAAGUGUUGGGAUUAUAGGCGUGAGCCACCACGCUUGGCCAAAUCUGGAGUCUAAAGGGUAUACAAGGUUUUUUUUUUUCCCAUGUUGGCUUUUAUUUGAUGUUAUAAAGUCUUCAUGAUAUGAAUAUAUUUUUUAAAAAGGUGUCAUGUAUAUUGUCAUGUAACAUGAUUCAUGCCACUUCAUUGUAUUAAAUACGUUUAAGAUACAGUUUUUGAUGUUAAGAAUGAUAUCCUGAGAAGGCCUAUCUCCUUCAGUCCUUUUCCCCAUUUUUCACCUUUUAACUCUUGCUUCUGAAUCUAUGCUAAGCUACUUACUAGAUGUGUGAUAUUGGUAGUUUUCUUACCUUAAAACCUCAUUUUCAUCAUCCAUGAAGAGGCUAACAAUAGUACUCCCUGUUGAUAGGAUUGUUGUAUUAAAAUAUAAGCAUUCAGCAUAGUGCCUGACUUAACGGUAGAGAUUCAAAUGGUAACCUCCUUCCAAUGCCUUCCUCCCCCCUUAACUCUGGAGAUUCCAUUUUUCUGUAGUGAAGUGUUUUAGAAUUUUCAUUGUUUGACUAUGGUUCAUACAUUGAUUUUUCCAAAAUGAGAAGAAGUCUUAUUUCUAAUGCAAAAAUGUGAAAAGAACAGUUGGAACCUAAAGUGAUAGUGGAUGAAGUGUCUGAAGUGACUGCCCUAUCAGAAAAGGAUGGAAUAAGAAGAAAAGACUGAAGCACCUAAAUGUGUAUUUUCUUGAGGAAAUUACACCCCUGUGUAAGAGUCUAUCCUAUUUGAACAUUUCUAAAAACCAGCCGAAGAAUCUUCAGGUUCAUUGCGACUGAAAGAUAAAGUCUAGCACUGAAGUGGUUUUUAAGAUUAGGAAAGGCCAUCAGAGAAAUGCAGUUAUUUCUCCCCUCCAUCCUUCCCCCACAAAAAAAAGUCUAAGCCUCCGAUUAAUCGACAACAACGAAAUACAGGAAGUAUUGGCUUAGUGACCUUUUAGGAUAUCUGUCCGACUUACAUCCCUUCUCUGAGCAUUACUUUCUGCCACCUUCCGUGAGGAGCUGUUCAGAAAUCAGACAAGGAGUGGACAUCUGGUCAAAGUUGAGCCAAUUAGAUGAUUUCUCCUGAGAAUUUGGAAUUGGAAAACUGAUGUCUUGGGAGGUCACAUCUGGAACAUACAUGGGAGGCAGAGAAAGCAAAGAUGACAUUCAACCCCAGAAGAAAAAGAAAAUGGCUUUCUUGAUUCCUGAUAACUUGGCAGUGUUUGUUCCAGUGUCUUGCAUUUCACUAUCUGCAUUUCAUCCUCCUGGGGUUCCACAAGAUAGCCUUAAAACCUUACAGAGAGACUCCCCAACUUAGUUUUUUCUUAAGUCAGAAGGCUGUUACUUGCUACCAAAUAAUGCCAACUAAGACAACUGAGGUACAGUAUAUUCUCUCGUAAAACACCAUAGAGUUGAUGACUUGAUCCUAUAGAAAAGGGUCCCCAACCCCUGGGCCACAGACCGGUACUGGUCCCUGGUCUGUGAGGAACCACCUGGGCCACAGACUGGUCCUGGUCCCUGGUCUGUGAGGAACCAGGCCAUACAGCAGGAGGUAAGCGAGCAUUCCUGCCUGAGCUCUGCCUCCUGUCAGAUGAGCCACAACAUUAGAUUCUCAUAGGAGUGCGAACCCCGUUGUGAACCCCGCAUGCGAGGGAUCUAGGUAGUGCCCUCCUUAAGAGAAUCUAAUGUCUGAUGAUCUGAGGUAGAGCAGUUUCAUCCUACAACCAUCCCCACCCCCCGACCCCCAUCCAUGAAAAAAUUGUCUUCCUCAAAACUAGUCCCUGGUGCCAAAAAGUUUGGGGACCGCCGUCCUAGGAAAUACCAACAAAAAGUCACGUUUAUUGCCUGCCAAGUGAGUCAGGUUUAGACAAGGCAGAACUUAGUAUAUAGCUUGGAUGAAUCAGAAAGGGUGGGCCUUGAAAGACUGGUAGAAUGUGUCCAAGAAAACUGAUUAAAAGCCUUAGAAGUCCCUCUACAGUUUCAGGACGCCCUCUUAACAGAUGGCUGUAUCUUUAUCUGUGGUUGGUCUUGUGGAAUACUGACUUUCUGCCAGCAUUAGCCUGUGUUUCUAUGUCACACCAAGUCACGUAUAUUUUCAUUGUGUGUUAGGACUCAGAAUAGGUUUGGGUCUUUCUUUUAAUUAUGUAUACCCAAUUACUUAGUCCUCCUCACACCCUGAUCCUUUAAAAAUUCUUAAGUUGUGUUAAUUGCAUUUUUCUCAAUUCUACUCCUAGUAACUCUGUGUGUUUUUUUCCAUCUUUAUUCAUUUAGUAAAGUUGAAACCUUUCAUAGCAUAAUAUAGUGAUUAAGUGCAUAGGUUUGGGACUUAGACACACAUGGGCUUGCUUGUCUCCCAGUUCUGCCGCUUACCACCUAUGUGACCUUUCACUCUUUACCUUUCCACUCUUAGCCUGUUCUCUAACUAUAAAAUGAGAAUGAUGCUAGCGUCAUCUUCAUAGAGUGAUUAUGGAGAUAAAUAAGUUAAUGCAUGUAAACCACUUUCCAUAAUGCCUGGCACAUAUUAUAUUAUGUAUUAGUAAAUGUAAGCACUGGAAGAAUCAGUAGUCUUCCUACACUUGAAAAUAGUUGUCUUCAACUAUUGUUGUAUUAAUGAGUUAAUUCACCUUGUUAAGUCACCUUGAUCCACCUAAUUGUCAGCCAACAUUUAUUAACGAAACUGCUAGUAUUCGUAUUGUGCCUUUUUUAUUAUGAAACAUUUCAAGAAUACAGAAAAAUGCAGAAAACAAUGUAACAAAUACCUAAGUAUCUAUCACCCAACUUUUAUAGUCUUAUUUUUACCUAUAUAUUUUUUCUUUUAGAAAGGAAUGAUCACAGUUGUGCCUGAAAUCUGUAUAGCCCUGUCUCAUUUCAUUUGUCUCCCUUUACCCACAUAAGUAAUUGCAGCUCUGAAUUUGAUGUUUAUCAGAAUGAUACCAUGAGUGGUUUUAUAUCCUUAUUAUAUGUAUGCAUACCUAGGAUUGUUUUUCUGAUUUUGAAACUUCAUAUAAAUGGUAUCAUUCUGUACAAAACCUUCUGGGACUUGUUUUACCACUCAUGUUUUUGAGAUGUAUCCACACUACCAUCUUUCUCUAAAUCAUUCAUUUAAAUGCUGUAGUUCAUUGAAUAAGUUUAUCACAAUGUAUCCAUUUUCUUCUUGAUGAGCAUCUCAGUUAUUUCCAAUUUUUGACUUAUAAACAAUGCUGCAAUGAAAUAAUUGACAUAUUUCCUUGUGUACAUGUGAGCAUUUCUUGAGAUAUGUAUCUAGAACUUGAAUCACUGGCCAACAGGAUAUUCUUAAUCUUCAGUUUCACCAGAUACUUCCAAAUUGAUCUCCAUAACAUGCAUACCAAAUUAUAUUCCUACCAGCCAUUUAUAGGAGUUCACAUUUUUUCCAUACCCUCCCAAUCCUGCCUUGGCAGAUAUGUUUUUUCCAAUGAAUAACAAUGAAAUUUUGUUUUGGGAUUUGACAAAAUGAUUCUAGAUUCAUCUGGAAGAAAAGCAAGUAUAAGUAAGAAAUUUAAAAGGGACCUGAAAAACUAAGCAAUGGAUAUAUUUAAAAAUUGGUACCAGUAGGGAUAACCAAAUAUUUGUUAACUGUAGCAGAAACAAUGCAUGUUUUUCUCACUGGUUCCACCUUCUAUCUCUCAGUCAAGCCCUGCCCAGGUGUGGUAGUCCUCAUAGUCUCUCACUGUAGGGGUCUUCUCACAUAGUAGACCACUCUCUUGAGUUGAAUAUUGAAAAGAAGGCUUGGCCGGGGGCAGUGGCUCAUGCCUGUGGUCCCAGCACUUUGGGAAGCUGAGUCGAGCGGAUUGCUUGAGGUCAGCAGUUCGAGAGCAGCCUGACUAACAUGGUGAUGAAAAGUACAAAAUUAGCUGGGGGUGGUGGCGCAUGCCUGCAAUCCCAGCUACUCGGGAGGCUGAGGCACGAGAAUCGCUUGAACGCAGGAGGCAUAGGUUGCAGUGAGCCGAGAUUGCACCACUGCACUCCAGCCUGGGCGACAGAGCAAGAUUUCGUCUCAAAAAAAAAAAAAAAAAAAAAAAAGGCUUAAGUCCAACUAACUGUUUCCCUGCUGUUCAUUUUAUCCAACGGCUGGGGAUAUAGGCUACUGCACAUGAUGGGUUGAUGGAUGUGAAAUGAUAACUCAUGACUUUAAUUCUAAUUUUUCUAUAUUCUGGUGAGGUUGAGCAUAUUUUUACAAGUUCAUAAUCCAUUUUCCUCUGAUGGGAGUUGCCUGUUUGAAUCCUUUGCCCACUUGCUUUUUGGGGUUAUUUGCAAUUUUUUGCAUUGAUCUUCAAACAUUCUUAAUUAAUCCCAGGUACAUAUUAUUUUAUAUAUAAGAUAUAUUUUAGAGAUAUAUAGGCUGAUAGUAUCUUUUCUCAGUCUAAGGCUUAUCUUUUAAUUUUGUUUAUGGUGUUUUGUGUGUGUUGUUUUGCAGAAGUUUUAUUGUAUCUGAAUUGUGGCUUUUGUGUCUUAAGAAAUUCUUUACCUACUGUCAUAAAAAUUUUUGUCUAAAAAUUUUAUGAUUUUGCCUUUCUAUUUAUCUUGUUAAUUCACUUUGAAAUUACUUUUGUUUAUGGCAUAAAGUCCAUUAUUUUCCAUAUGGAUAAUCAGUUGUCUUAGCAGUUUAUUGAAUGGUCCAACGUUUCCCUGCUGAUUAUAAUGCCCUCUCUGUUAUUUAUCCUAAAUUCUUGACAUCCGGUAAGGAAGUCUCCUCUGCCCACCCUUCUCUGUAUUUCAAAAUGGUUUUGACUGUUCUUGACCCCUUGCUCUUUCUGUGAACUUUAGGAUUAAAUGAUUAUGUAGAAUUAAACAAUCGGGUUAAGGUUUUUUAUUAGAAUUACAUUGAAUCUAUAGAUUAAUUUGGGGAAAGAAUGUUAUCUUUCUAUCCAUGAUAAUUCUGUAUCUCUCCAUUAAUUCAAGUCUUUAAUGGUUUUUAAAAAUAAAUUAUUGUCUCUUUGAAAA